AGGCGCGGGGAGCCUCCCCCUUCGACUGCAGCCUCGCUCCGUGCCUUCUGCGCGCCUGGGAUCCCGGAGCCUGCCUAGGUUCUGUGCGCUCCCGCCCAGGCCGGUGCCCGCCGCCCGCCUGCGCCCCAGGCAGGUCCCAGGCCUCCGGCUGCUCCCGGCCGAAGGUGGGGACAGGCAGUGGCAGGCACCACUAGCGAGGGCGUUUGGGAACCCAGGGUGACCACGGCGCAGCCAUGGGGACCGCGCUUGUGUACCAUGAGGACAUGACGGCCACCCGGCUGCUCUGGGACGACCCCGAGUGCGAGAUCGAGCGUCCUGAGCGCCUGACCGCAGCCCUGGAUCGCCUGCGGCAGCGCGGCCUGGAACAGAGGUGUCUGCGGUUGUCAGCCCGCGAGGCCUCGGAAGAGGAGCUGGGCCUGGUGCACAGCCCAGAGUAUGUAUCCCUGGUCAGGGAGACCCAGGUCCUAGGCAAGGAGGAGCUGCAGGCGCUGUCCGGACAGUUCGACGCCAUCUACUUCCACCCGAGUACCUUUCACUGCGCGCGGCUGGCCGCAGGGGCUGGACUGCAGCUGGUGGACGCUGUGCUCACUGGAGCUGUGCAAAAUGGGCUUGCCCUGGUGAGGCCUCCCGGGCACCAUGGCCAGAGGGCGGCUGCCAACGGGUUCUGUGUGUUCAACAACGUGGCCAUAGCAGCUGCACAUGCCAAGCAGAAACACGGGCUACACAGGAUCCUCGUCGUGGACUGGGAUGUGCACCAUGGCCAGGGGAUCCAGUAUCUCUUUGAGGAUGACCCCAGCGUCCUUUACUUCUCCUGGCACCGCUAUGAGCAUGGGCGCUUCUGGCCUUUCCUGCGAGAGUCAGAUGCAGACGCAGUGGGGCGGGGACAGGGCCUCGGCUUCACUGUCAACCUGCCCUGGAACCAGGUUGGGAUGGGAAACGCUGACUACGUGGCUGCCUUCCUGCACCUGCUGCUCCCACUGGCCUUUGAGUUUGACCCUGAGCUGGUGCUGGUCUCGGCAGGAUUUGACUCAGCCAUCGGGGACCCUGAGGGGCAAAUGCAGGCCACGCCAGAGUGCUUCGCCCACCUCACACAGCUGCUGCAGGUGCUGGCCGGCGGCCGGGUCUGUGCCGUGCUGGAGGGCGGCUACCACCUGGAGUCACUGGCGGAGUCAGUGUGCAUGACAGUACAGACGCUGCUGGGUGACCCGGCCCCACCCCUGUCAGGGCCAAUGGCGCCAUGUCAGAGUGCCCUAGAGUCCAUCCAGAGUGCCCGUGCUGCCCAGGCCCCGCACUGGAAGAGCCUCCAGCAGCAAGAUGUGACCGCUGUGCCGAUGAGCCCCAGCAGCCACUCCCCAGAGGGGAGGCCUCCACCUCUGCUGCCUGGGGGUCCAGUGUGUAAGGCAGCUGCAUCUGCACCGAGCUCCCUCCUGGACCAGCCGUGCCUCUGCCCCGCACCCUCUGUCCGCACCGCUGUUGCCCUGACAACGCCGGAUAUCACAUUGGUUCUGCCCCCUGACGUCAUCCAACAGGAAGCGUCAGCCCUGAGGGAGGAGACAGAAGCCUGGGCCAGGCCACACGAGUCCCUGGCCCGGGAGGAGGCCCUCACUGCACUUGGGAAGCUCCUGUACCUCUUAGAUGGGAUGCUGGAUGGGCAGGUGAACAGUGGUAUAGCAGCCACUCCAGCCUCUGCUGCAGCAGCCACCCUGGAUGUGGCUGUUCGGAGAGGCCUGUCCCACGGAGCCCAGAGGCUGCUGUGCGUGGCCCUGGGACAGCUGGACCGGCCUCCAGACCUCGCCCAUGACGGGAGGAGUCUGUGGCUGAACAUCAGGGGCAAGGAGGCGGCUGCCCUAUCCAUGUUCCAUGUCUCCACGCCACUGCCAGUGAUGACCGGUGGUUUCCUGAGCUGCAUCUUGGGCUUGGUGCUGCCCCUGGCCUAUGGCUUCCAGCCUGACCUGGUGCUGGUGGCGCUGGGGCCUGGCCAUGGCCUGCAGGGCCCCCACGCUGCACUCCUGGCUGCAAUGCUUCGGGGGCUGGCAGGGGGCCGAGUCCUGGCCCUCCUGGAGGAGAACUCCACACCCCAGCUAGCAGGGAUCCUGGCCCGGGUGCUGAAUGGAGAGGCACCUCCUAGCCUAGGCCCUUCCUCUGUGGCCUCCCCAGAGGACGUCCAGGCCCUGAUGUACCUGAGAGGGCAGCUGGAGCCUCAGUGGAAGAUGUUGCAGUGCCAUCCUCACCUGGUGGCUUGAAAUCGGCCAAGGUGGGAGCAUUUACACCGCAGAAAUGACACCGCACGCCAGCGCCCCGCGGCCGCGAUCCGGACCCCAAGCCCACGGCUCCCUCGACUCUGGGGCACGGAACCCCGCCCACUCCCAAUCCCCGCGCCCCGCCCUCUCCCACCCGUGCUUCCCCCGCUCCACCCCUCACCUCACCUCGCCCCCGCCCCACCCAUCGCGCCCCGGCCCGUCCCAUCGAGGCCCAUGCAACCCACGCUCGGUCCCGUUCCGGCCCCUGCGCCCCGCUGCGCUUCGCUCCCCGCCCUUGCGCCGUUAGUAAACAUCGCUCAAACGAAA